AGUGAGGCCAGCACCAUGGACAACCCACAGGCUCUGCCACUCUUCCUACUCCUGGCCUCCUUGGUAGGGAUCCUCACCCUCAGAGCCUCUUCUGGACUUCAGCAAACCAACUUCUCCUCUGCCUUCUCUUCAGACUCAAAGAGCUCUUCCCAGGGGCUGGGUGUGGAAGUUCCCUCCAUCAAACCUCCCAGCUGGAAAGUUCCAGAUCAGUUCCUGGAUUCAAAAGCCUCUGCUGGAAUCUCUGAUUCCAGCUGGUUUCCUGAGGCCCUGAGUUCCAACAUGUCUGGGUCCUUCUGGUCAAAUGUUUCUGCUGAGGGCCAAGAUUUGAGCCCGGUUUCCCCCUUCUCUGAAACCCCUGGUUCUGAAGUAUUUCCUGAUAUUUCGGAUCCUCAAGUUCCUGCCAAAGACCCCAAGCCUUCCUUCACUGUUAAGACCCCAGCUUCAAACAUUUCUACUCAAGUCUCCCAUACCAAACUGUCUGUUGAGGCCCCAGAUUCAAAAUUCUCCCCGGAUGAUAUGGAUCUUAAACUCUCUGCCCAGAGCCCUGAAUCCAAAUUUUCUGCAGAGACCCACUCAGCUGCAAGCUUUCCCCAGCAGGUGGGGGGCCCACUCGCUGUGCUGGUGGGGACCACCAUCCGGCUCCCCCUAGUCCCAAUCCCCAACCCUGGGCCCCCCACCUCUCUGGUGGUCUGGCGCCGGGGCUCAAAGGUGCUGGCAGCUGGGGGCCUGGGGCCAGGGGCACCUCUGAUCAGCCUGGACCCUGCUCACCGAGACCACCUGCGAUUUGACCAGGCCCGGGGGGUUCUGGAGCUCGCCUCUGCCCAGCUGGACGAUGCAGGGGUCUACACGGCUGAGGUCAUCCGGGCAGGGGUCUCCCAGCAGACUCACGAGUUCACGGUGGGUGUGUAUGAGCCCCUACCCCAGCUGUCGGUUCAGCCCAAGGCUCCAGAGACAGAGGAGGGGGCGGCCGAGCUCCGGCUGCGCUGCCUGGGGUGGGGGCCAGGUCGCGGGGAGCUGAGCUGGAGCCGGGACGGACGCGCCCUGGAGGCGGCGGAAUCGGAGGGAGCCGAGACGCCCCGGAUGCGCUCAGAGGGCGACCAGCUGCUCAUCGUGCGCCCUGUGCGCAGCGACCACGCCCGGUACACUUGCCGCGUCCGCAGCCCCUUCGGCCACAGGGAGGCUGCCGCCGACGUCAGCGUCUUCUACGGCCCGGACCCGCCGACCAUCACGGUCUCCUCGGACCGCGACGCCGCGCCUGCCCGCUUUGUCACCGCGGGCAGUAACGUGACCUUGCGCUGCGCCGCCGCCUCGCGGCCGCCCGCCGACAUCACGUGGAGCCUGGCGGACCCGGCCGAGGCCGCGGUGCCCGCGGGGUCGCGCCUCCUGCUGCCCGCGGUCGGACCGGGCCACGCAGGCACCUACGCCUGCCUGGCGGCGAACCCGCGUACCGGCCGCCGCCGCCGCUCGCUGCUCAACCUUACAGUGGCGGACCUGCCCCCCGGGGCCCCACAGUGCUCAGUUGAAGGGGGUCCCGGGGACCGCAGCCUCCGCUUCCGCUGCUCGUGGCCCGGCGGGGCCCCUGCUGCCUCCCUGCAGUUCCAGGGUCUCCCCGAAGGCAUCCGCGCCGGGCCAGUGUCCUCUGUGCUGCUGGCGGCCGUCCCCGCCCACCCCCGGCUCAGCGGCGUCCCCAUCACCUGCCUUGCUCGCCACCUGGUGGCCACGCGUACCUGCACAGUCACGCCGGAGGCCCCCCGAGAGGUGCUGCUGCAUCCGCUGGUGGCAGAGACACGGUUGGGGGAGGCAGAGGUGGCACUGGAGGCCUCUGGUUGUCCCCCACCCUCACGGGCAUCCUGGGCCCGGGAAGGGAGGCCCCUGGCUCCAGGAGGCGGGAGUCGCCUGCGGCUCAGUCAAGAUGGGCGGAAACUCCACAUCGGCAACUUCAGCCUGGAUUGGGACCUGGGAAAUUACUCCGUGCUGUGCAGUGGGGCGCUGGGUGCUGGCGGUGACCAGAUCACCCUCAUUGGACCCUCCAUAUCCUCGUGGAGGCUUCAGAGAGCCAGAGAUGCAGCCGUGCUGACUUGGGAUGUGGAGCGCGGGGCCCUGAUCAGCAGUUUUGAGAUCCAGGCAUGGCCAGAUGGGCCUGCUCUGGGCAGGACUUCCACCUACAGGGACUGGGUCUCCCUGCUCAUCCUGGGGCCUCAGGAGCGGUCAGCCGUGGUGCCCCUUCCACCUCGGAACCCAGGGACCUGGACCUUUCGGAUCCUGCCCAUCCUGGGGGGCCAGCCAGGGACUCCAUCACAAAGCCGGGUCUACCGGGCCGGCCCCACGUUGAGCCAUGGGGCCAUCGCUGGCAUCGUCCUGGGCUCCCUGCUGGGCCUGGCGCUGCUAGCCGUACUUCUCCUCCUUUGCAUCUGCUGCCUGUGCCGCUUUCGUGGAAAGACUCCUGAGAAAAAGAAGCAUCCUUCUACCUUGGUCCCCGUGGUCACCCCCUCAGAAAAGAAGAUGCAUAGUGUGACCCCAGUGGAGAUUUCAUGGCCUCUGGACCUCAAAGUCCCUCUGGAGGACCACAGCUCAACUAGGGCCUACCAAGCACAGACCCCAGUUCAGUUGUCUCUGUAGGCGGAGGCUCAAAGACUGUUCGCGCAGCCACACAGGUGUGAUCAGAGCCAGUGGUCUGCCCUGCACAGGGCGUUUUGGGCCAGAACUUCCUAUUUCACUCCAGCAGCAGCCAGGGCCUGCUAUGACUGAGGGUUGGACCCUGAAAGUGGGACUUUCUGUCUCCCUCUCUUGCUGCAGAAGAAGAGUCUUCCUGUAUUUGUGCAAGUAAGGAGAUGUGACUUCUUGGCUGGGAAACUCUUGCUGAUCUAACUGUGUGGUUUGCACAACCUCCAAGCCUCUGCAGCAGACAGGCAGGGCUUGCUGUGUUGCUCUGAGCUAGAGAGGGAGCUUGGCCAUGUUCUCUGAAAAGGUCCCCUUACAUUCACUUUGCCACCUGUAGGCCACACCCCAUCCAGCUCCCAGCAUCUUCAUCUUAAAACAGAUCAGAUCAUGUCACUCUUCUCUUUAAACGCUUCUACGGCCUGUGCAUUUCCCUUCAGAUAUUAUCCAAACUCAUCGUCGUGACCUUCAAAACCUUGUGGUCUGGCCUCUGUUGGCCUCCCUGACCUCCCCUCCCAAUUCUUUCUCUGCCCCCGGACUCCAGUAUCACAGUCUGUCUCUCAGCCACAAUUUAUUUUGCCCCUAGAGUUUGCUGUGCUUAUAACACUUCUUUUUCCCAUAUGUCAUUCAUUUCUCAAGUCUAAGAGUAGCAGUUACCAUCUUAGACGACCGUUCCCUUACCCCUCCCUUAGUCUUGGGUUAAGUCCCAGAAUCCUUGAAUUUGCCGUUCCUGAUACAUAAAUAUGUAAUUUCUUGUGUGGCCUGAGACUCUCUCUCUAAACUAAGGGCUUUACAAAAGCAGAGACCACAUCAUUAACUCAGCACUUAACCCAGAGCCUCACACACAGCAGGCAAUCAAUAAAUAUUUGUUGACUGAUCAAAUGUUUUGGUGCCAGUGAAGAGUUGGGCUUGCUGCUGCUGUCUUCAGCGUAAGUCUUGCUUUUUCAGCUGGGUUUCUAAUUGAGAAUUUAGAGAGUGCAUUGGUGAGGAUUCUUUUGACUGCAAGUAACAAAAUAAAAUGGUGGCAAGAA